ACACCAGCCUUGAGCCCAGCCUGCGGCCAGGGGACCACGCACGUCCCACCCACCCAGCGACUCCCCAGCCGCUGCCCACUCUUCCUCACUCAUGGGGAACAGCAAAAGUGGGGCCCUGUCCAAGGAGAUCCUGGAGGAGCUGCAGCUGAACACCAAGUUCUCGGAGGAGGAGCUGUGCUCCUGGUACCAGUCCUUCCUGAAGGACUGUCCCACCGGCCGCAUCACCCAGCAGCAGUUCCAGAGCAUCUACGCCAAGUUCUUCCCCGACACCGACCCCAAGGCCUACGCCCAGCAUGUGUUCCGCAGCUUCGAUUCCAACCUCGACGGCACCCUGGACUUCAAGGAGUACGUCAUCGCCCUGCACAUGACCACCGCGGGCAAGACCAACCAGAAGCUGGAGUGGGCCUUCUCCCUCUACGACGUGGACGGUAACGGGACCAUCAGCAAGAAUGAAGUGCUGGAGAUCGUCAUGGCUAUUUUCAAAAUGAUCACUCCCGAGGACGUGAAGCUCCUUCCAGACGAUGAAAACACGCCGGAAAAGCGAGCCGAGAAGAUCUGGAAGUACUUUGGAAAGAAUGAUGAUGAUAAACUUACAGAGAAAGAAUUCAUUGAGGGGACACUGGCCAAUAAGGAAAUUCUGCGACUGAUCCAGUUUGAGCCUCAAAAAGUGAAGGAAAAGAUGAAGAACGCCUGAUGCCAACUGUUCAGCUGUCCUCCCUCCACCUACCACUCACAUGACACCCGUGAGCGCCUGUGCACACACACACACAUGCACACACACGCGCGCGCACACACACACACACACAUCCACCCCAGGGCCAAGAGAAAGGCCUGCACACAAGCCCACAGCACAGCUCCCUGCCAAACUGAAGCAUCUGUAGUGACCCACUGGUUCCUUCUUCCUGGGUCUUCAGCAUUCCCUCCCAUCAUGCCCGGUCCCACCCCUCCCUCUGUCCACCAGCCCAUGGCCCUGUGCUAAUCCCAGGAUUAGGCCAUAGGAGUCCUAAGUGUCACCCCGCUGUAAGCUCCUUUGUGGAGUGCUGGGUAAGCAGUUUCCAAUAAACGCAAGCUGAGCUGGGCACGUGGCUGCUGGUCAUCCUUCAACUGGAAAAGGAAAUGAUUUCUAUCAGUCACACCUCAAAGACAAGGCUGUGUUGCGAUGGCAGCCCUAGGCUGGGCUGCUUUGGUGCGGAAUGAGUCUAAUGCGGUCCUGCUGUCAUGGAGCUCAUGGUCCAGAGGGGACAAUGAACCUGGAAGGAGCCAUGACCAGUGGCCCAGGUUACCAUGGAAACGUGCAGAGCACCAGGGGAGGACACAGUGGAAGGGGCUGACUUGUCAGGGGGGAUCAGGGACCACAUCCCUGACGAAGGGAGAUUUAAAUUCAGAACCACUGCACACGAGGCGGGGGACGGGGUCGGGGUGGGGAAGUCUCAAACAGAAGGCGGCCAACACAGAGCCGCUGAGGCAUGAAUGACCAUCUCGAGUUCCAGGAGAAGGUCGGGGUGGCUGGAGGGUAGAAGGAGGAGGGAGAGCAAAGUGUGAGCUGAAUCUAAAAGGUAGGCGGGGGCUGGACCACGCAAAGCCCUCCCUGCAGCCUGUGGUAAGCACUUGGGGGCUCACCAUGGGGACAGCGGUGCCACUGUGGAGUUGGAAGUAGGAGGGGUUUAUGUUUGUAAGAGAAGUCCCCAGCAGGCUAAAAUAAGUCAGAGAGGAGCAACUGGGGGCUCCCUGGAGUCAGGGAGCCCGAUGAAUAAGCUUUUGCAGCCACUCAGAUGGCCUGGGCCAGGGGAAAGGCAAUGGGAUGGAGAGGACCAGAUCCAGUGAGGACACAUUUAGGAGGUAGCAUCCACCUGGCUGGCUGAGGGGGCAGGAGGAGAGAGGGCAGGAAUGGCAGCCAGGCCUGUAGCUUGGGCAGUGGGUGAAUAGCAAUGCCAUCUAUGGAGAUGAGAAAUACAGAGAGUCUUUGGGGUUUCAGGGAACAAUGAUGAAUUCAGCUUCAAUAUAGUAUGAGGUGAAGGCAGAGCCAUAGAUGGCCCUAAAGCCCCUUGUUUUAGAGACAAGGAAAAGGAGUCCCAAUGACAGGAAGCAGCUUGCCCAAGGGCAGCCAGCUGAUGAGCAGAGGUCAGGCAAGGGCUACCCACCGGCCCCCAACUGCCUCCUCAAAGCUCCAGGGCCUGGGAUACCCAGGAACUCCAUCAGUGCAUUCUCCAAGAUCCCUGGAUUUGUUGCUUUGAAGGCCCAUUUAUUCUCCAGCCUCAAGUUCCAAGAUGAGGUCAGAAAAAUGCAUGGAUACCCUGGAUUCUUGACUGACCUGUCUGCAACCUCUUGAGGCUGAGGAGUCUCUAGUUGCUGGUAUUGUGGUGAUGCCUCCAGACCCCACUUUAGCCACAGAGAUGACACAAUCACCACUGCCAAAGAGCACUCCUCUGUGUGGAGAGCAAACGUGAGAAUAAACACUUAUGAACCGUG